GAACCCCACUCUGGCCCGGGCAGGGGUGCAGCUCGCGGAAUGCCCCAGAGGGCCGCCGCCCCGCGCACGCGGCUGUGUGCGCCCGAGCACGCCCGCUGCGCCCCCUCUCCGCGCCGCAAUCACGGGUUCGCGCCGCGCCUUCAGUCAGGCGCGGGCGCCGAGGCCAUUUUGUCUGAGGCUCGGGUCCCGGCCGUCGAGCACAAGAGUGUAGCUGCACCCAGUGGCUGUCCCGCGCCCACCCCGGAGCUCCGAGAAGCUCUGGAACCAGAUCGUUACCACCCGUGCCUGGCUGUCCGGCCUACCCCACGCCCGCCCGGAUCUGGAGGCGAACCCGCCACCGCCGCGCCCUCCCCGUAUCCGGCUCCGCAGUGACACGCGCAGCCCUCGCCCCACCCCGGGCCACGUCUCCCGCUCCCAGUGCAGCCACUCUCCUCCGGCCGAACAAAGAGGCCCCGGGACGCCGCGGAGCCUGCCAUGCCCGGACGGGUCGCGCCAGACCAAAGGGCCAAGGGCGGAGGCGGCGGUCACAAAGCGGCUUUUGUGCCACCCACCCGGCCCGCUGCGGAAGCCGAAACUGCCCCCGGCCGCCGCAGAAGCCGGACCGCGCCGCCCCCGUCGCUCCGGGCUCGGGAGGGACUCAAAAGCCGGUGCCUCCGGCGGCCAACCGCCACCCCGCAGCCCCGAGGGGCCCGGCAUCUGCCUCCGCACAGCCGGCCGCAAUCGGCCGGCCACAGGGCCAUAACCCGCCCGCUCCCACCCGGGACCCACCGGAACCGCAACCCGGGGCAACCUGGAGGAGACGCCGGGCUCCGAACAAAGGCGACAGCGGGGAUGGGGGGCCGGUCGUGGAUUCCCAGCCCGAGAGGCGACGAUGCGACGGCUACUCACAGGAAUAUGUUUACUCAUUGAAGAUUGUGGCCUAAUCAUACAGCCGGUCCCGAGGCGGCGGCGACACAGGCGGUGGCGGUGGCUGCAGGGCAGGAGGCGGCGGUGGUCGUGGCGGAGCGGCGGUGGCGGCGAUGCAGGCGGCGGCGGGGGCACCAGACUCUACCAUGCAGUGAGCGGCUCGGAGCAGAGCGCGUAGCCGAGCCGGCCCGCAGCCGAAGGAGCCAAUACACGCGCCGAGGCGCCCUUGCGUCACAAGCCCUCCCCUUUAUAGCCGGCGCGACGUGCAACCCUCCAGCCACCAAUCGCGGCCUGGAACCGCGGGCCAGGAGCCGACAGGCGGGGGCGGAGGCCCGCCCCCUCCGGACGUCACUCCGCGGCGGCCGCCGCCGGUGUGAACCGGUUGAUGAAUGGCUAAGCGCCGAGUCGGAGCAUCCCCGGGGCGGGGGAGGGAAGGGGCUGCCGGGAGUGCUCCGGGAUGCAGGAAGCCUGAAGUUAAGAAGGGGUGGGAGCGAGAGAGAUUCCGAUUUAUCGACUGGAAGGAAUCAUGCUGCAAACCACGUUUCUCAUAAUUAAAACGGUCCAGGAGUGCACACAUGUCACAUGAGGAGACUCGAAGUUUGCCUGAAUCGUAAAAUGCAAUCCUUCUAGGGCUGGAACCGCGUCUCAGUGUCGAGCCUGCUUUCUACUGCCUUAACCACGGUCAUCUUUGCCAGUGGUUUACCUUGGCACCUGGGCCCCGAGUACCUUCGUCAUCAAAUAAUAUUUAUGUCGCAAGACCGCUGUACCCGGUGACUCAACACCUUGCAUGCCACGGCCUUAGGCUUGGUCAAGAUGAAUUCUUGUCCCUGGGGGCGCUUUCAAGCGGGGAGAAACUUACCUUCGCAAAACUUAAGGCUAUAGAAGAUGGGGAGAGUAUCUUUUGAUGCAGACGAAGCCCUAUGCUCCCUAUAUUCUUUUUUUGAUCACACCUCUCUAUACUACGUACGCGUGCAACUGCAGUUGGCUCAAUUGUGGCAUUUCGAAAUCACAUGCAUCCUUUGUACUGCUGCUCACUUGAUAUGUUGUCUCAGAUAAUGAAAGGUUAGGAAGUGCUUAAAGAAAGCGUUUUUAGAAAUUAAGAAUCCUCGGUUUUGUCAAGCACUGAUGUAAUUCUUUGCGUCAAAGCUAAAGCUCUUCUUUAUGUUCGUUUUCAGUCCUCUUUUACUGACUUCAUUAUUUAAGCCCCUAAGAAGUAAAGUCUUAUCGCAAUUCUGUGCCAUACAAGGGCACCUCUGUUAUUUAUAAUCUGAAAACCCUUUCUCCUCAGCUCUGGAGAAGGACCAAACAGGACCUUUACCUGCUUUUUAAGAACUCAGUUUUCCACUAACACUGAAGCCUUUUGUUUGUUAUUUUCACCGAGUAUGAGAUUGGAGAGGGCUUUAGGGAUCAAAUUUUGUCCUCUUUCAGUGCCCUGCAACAUCUUAGGAUUUAUUAGAACUUCUAUUUAGAGACUGGUUGUAUAGUUAUUCAACUUUCUUAACUCUGUAAGUAAAAUAAGAACUUUAAAAAAACAAAAACAAACAAAAUCCUGGGCCAGACUUUCAAAGGAACAAAAACUCUUCGUCAUUUGGAAGAAAAUGGCUCACCUACGACACAUUUUAAUCCAUUAAAAUCAAGGAAAACUAGCACACUUGAGAAAUAUGUCCCUUUACAAAUAAAUGAUUUAAAAAAGUAAAGACUUUAAAAUCUUAAAUUCUAAGAAAAUAUAGAAAGCUUAAAAAUCUUGGGUGGUAGGGGCAAAGCUAAGCAGGCUGGGGAACUCAUGUCGAAAAAAAGGGACAGAUUUCAUAUAUAAGAACUAAAAACUUUUAUAUGGCAAAAGGCUUUUGACAAAUGUCAAUUUCACACUGGGGGAAAUAUUGGUGAUACUUCAUGGGUAGGGUUAAUAUAAAAAGCUUGGCCAAUGUAUAUAAUAGUGUAGUUAAAAAGCACAUAUUCAGUCAGCCACUCUUACUCCACAAGUUGGUAAACACAGAUAAUUGGAAUAGUGAAACUUUUUCAUGUAAUGGCAUUUCAAAAAAUACAUUUGGUGGGACAAGAUAUAAACUCAGCAAAUGAUUAACAGAGCCAAAUAUGUGUUAGCCAAUUUUCUUGUAGAACUUGUGAUACAAGUUGUGAGCCUUGUGAUCCACAGAUCCUGUAAUUACCACAAGCAGUGCUGACACGAAGUAUCCAGUCAGCUAUGCUCAUCAAGUUCUAAAAGCUCUCAAAUUCUCAAGUGGCCUGGGGGUCUUAGCCUCUCAGACAAGGUACCAUCUUAUCCUACUAUGAAAGUAACAUAUUUAAAGGAUGAAAAAAUAAGGCUUUUGCUGUUGAGAGAAACGAUGCAUUUUAUUUUAUGUAUUUAUUUGAGAUGGAGUCUUGCUCUUUUGCCCAGGUUGGAGCACAGUGGUGCAAUCUUUGCUCACUGCAACCUCAGCCUCCUGGGUUCCAGCAAUUCUCCUGCCUCAGCCUCCCAAGUAGCUGGGAUUACAGCCACCUGCCACCACACCUGGCUAAUUUGUUUGUACUUUUAGAAAACUCCAUGUUGACUAGGCUAGUUUUGAACUCCUGACCUCAAGAGAUCUGCCUGCCUCAGUCUCCCAAAGGAAAGGACACAUUUUAAACAAGAUAUAAGUGUGGUCUUGCUGACCAAUCCAUUAAAUGUUCCUGCUUGUCAGCUGCCAUUGUGGUUCACUGCUAUGCUGAGGGUGUCUGCUGUAUUUAGUUUAAUACUUUUAAGCUGCAGAUUCUUGGAGAACAGUAGAACAUCCCAGCAUUGGUCAGGAGACUUCUGUGAUUUGAGGACUCACUAACCCUUACAGACUUGCACUCAGAGCAUUAGCACCUGUACUUAUUUAAAGUGGGUCUCUAACAGACUUGAAAAUAGUGCUUCCAGACAUCAAAAAGGGAGAAAACACCUCUAAAAGCCAAUGCUUACUCUAAGCUCCAGGAGAGGCUCUAAAAUAGAGGAUUUUCUCUCCUGCUAAACAAGAUUCUCAGCUGGAAGUUACUUCUCUCAGCAAAACAUGUGUCCUUAACCUCAUCACGAUAGGCAGGGCUUUCUAUUGACAAUUCAAAAUAUAAAAGCCAGCAGUUGGGAAAUAAGACUAGAAGAAUAUUAUAAGGAAGUUGAGCAUGGUGGCAUACAGGCUCAUGCCUGUAAUCCCAGUACUUUGGGAGACCAAGGUGGGUGGAUCACCUGAGAUUAGGAGUUAGGAGUUCAAGACCAGCCUGGUCAACAUGGUGAAACCCAUCUCUACUAAAAAUACAAAAAAUUAGCUGGGCAUGGUGGCAGGCACCUCUAAUCCCAGUUACUUGGGAGGCUGAAGAAGGAGAAUCACUGGAAAGCUGGGAGGCAGAGGCUGCAGUGAGCCGAGAUCAUGGCACUGCACUCUAGCCUGGGAGACAGAGUGAGACUUCAUUUCAAAAAAAGAAUAUUAUAAGCGAUAUUUUUAUGGAAGAGGAAAGACUGCAGAAGGCAAGAGUGCAGAGGAAGAUUGGCAAAUCUUGAUGAAGAAGAACAGAGAAAUCUUCACAAGAACAGCAGAUCUAGUAAACAUUGAUUCCAUUUUACCAAGUUUACAAAAGGAGUGAAGGAUUCCUUGAUUUUCAAUCUUCUCAGAUUGGUUGGGGCUACAAGGAAGUCUGAUAAAAACAUUUAACAUAGCAAGAGUAAUAUCAUUGCCAUAAUAGAUUAAACGUGACAAUAUCAACCUAGAAAAAGACACUAGAUUGCAAGGUAUAAUGACAGUCUAGCAAAUAUAUGUAAUAGAGGCAAAUACCCCAAUGGGCCAUAAUCUAGUAAGUGUCUGGAUACUAGUGCAGAGGGUAAGUUCCCAUACCCAUAUUUAACAAGAGUCCUAAAAAUUCAAGUAUGCCAUGGCUGCUGUCAGCAUUGUUAAAGUUUAUUUCCCUCUUGCUGUUUUAGAACAGCCUAUUUUAUAUCCAAUUAAUUUUCUUAUAUGAUUAUUAAAAAUAAAUAUGUAGUAUACAGGCAUACCUUCAUUUAUUGUGCUUUGCAAAUAUUGUUUUUUUUUUUUAACAAAAUGAUGGUUUGUGACAGCUUUUUGUCGAGCAAGUCUAUCAGAGCCAUUUUUCCAAUAGCAUGUGCUCAUUUCAUGUCUCUGUGUUACAUCUUGGUAAUUCUCCCAAUAUUUCAAACUUUUAAAUUAUUAUUGCAUUUGUUAUGGCAAUUUGUGAACAGUGAUCUUUGAUAUUGUUAUUGGAAUUGUUUUGGGCCACCACAAACUGUACCCAUUUAAGAUGGCAAACUUAUUUGAUAAAUGUUGAAUAUAUUCUGACUGCUCCGCUGAUGGGCCAGUCCCUCAGUGAGACACAGCAAUACUGAAAUUAGGCCAAUUAAUAACCCUACAGUGGCCUCUGAGUGUUCAAGUGAAAGGAAGAGUCAUUCAUCUCUCACUUUAAAUCAAAGCUAAAAAUGAUUAAGCUGAGUAAGGCAAGUUGAAAGCAGAGAUAGGCCGAAAACUAGGCCUCAUACCCAAAACAGUCAAGUUGUGAAUGCCAAGGAAAAGCUCUUGAAGGAAGUUAAAAGUGCCACUCCAGUGAACACAGGAAUGAUAAGAAAGUGAAACAGCCUCAUUGUUGAUAAGGAGAAAGUUUUAGAGUUCUGGAUAGAAAACCAGCCACAGCAUUCUCUUAAGUCAAAGCCUAAUUCAGAGCAAGGCCUUAACUCUCUUCAUUUUUAUGAAGGCUGAGAGAGGUGAGGAAGUUGUAGAAGAAAAGUCUGAAGAUAGCAGAGGUGGAUUCAUGAGGUUUAAGAGUAGAAGCCCUCUCCCUAACAUAAAAAUGAAAGGUGAAGCAGUAAGUGCUGAUGGAGAAGCUGCAGCAAGUUAUUGAGAAGAUUUAGCCAAGAACAUUGAUGAAGGUGGCUACACUAAAUAACAGAUUUUCAAUGUAGACAAAACAGUCUUAUACUGGAAGAAGAUGCUGUCCAAGACUUUCAUAGCUAUAGAAGUCAAUGCUUGGCUUCAAAGCUUCGAAGGACAGGCAGUUCUCUUGUUAGGGGCUGAUGUGGCUGGUGACUUUAAGUUGAAGCAGAUGUUCAUUUACCAUUCUGAAAAUCCUAGGACCCUUAAAAAUUAUGCUAAAUCUACUCUGCUGUGCUCUAUAAGUGGAAGAACAAAACCUGGUUGACAGCACAUCUGUUUAGCAUGGCUCACUAAAUAUUUUAAGUCCACUGUUGAGACCUACUGAUAAAACGUGAUUUAUUUAAAAAUACUAUUGCUCCUUGACAAUGCACAUGGUCACUGAAAUGCUCUGAUGGAGAUGUACAAGGAGAGUAAUAUUGUUUUCAUGCCUUCUAACACAGCAUCCAUUCUGCAACCCAUGGAUCAAGGAAUAAUUUUGACUUUCAGGUUUUAAUAUUUAACAAGUACAUUUCAUAAGGUUAUAAAUUGCUGUAGAUGGUGAUUCCUCUGAUGGAUCUAAGCAAAGUAAACCAAAAACAUUCUGGAAAGGAUUCUAGAUGCCAUUAAGAACAUUCAUGAGAGGAGGUAAAAGUAUCAGCAUGAACAGGAGUUUGAAAGAAGUUAACUCCAACUCUCAUGGAUGACCUUGAGGGCGUUCAAGACUUCAGUGGAGGAAAUCACUACAAAUAUGGUGAAAAUAGCAAGACAAUUGGAGUUAGAAACAGAGUCUGAAGAGUUGACUAAAUCGCUGCAAUUUUAUGAUCAAACUUGAAUGAAUGAGGAGUUGCUUCUUAUGAAGGAGAAAAGAGAGUGGUUUCUUGAGAUAGAAUCUACUGCUGGUGAAGAUGCCGUAAGCAUUGUUGAAAUGAUAAAGGAUUUAGAAUAUCACAUAAACUUAGCUGAUAAAGCAGUGGGUGAGUUUUAAGAGGACUGAUUGCAACUUUGAAAGGAGUUCUCUUGUGUGUAAAAUACUAUCAAACAGCACUGCCUGCUACAGAGAAAUUUUUUGUGGAGUCAUCAAUGCAGCAAACUCCAUUGUCUUAUUUCAAGAAAUUGCCACAGCCACCUUAACCUUCAGCAACUACCUCCCUGAUCAGUCAGCUGCCAUCAUCACUGAGGCAGGAUUCUCCAACAGCAAAGAUUAUGACUUGCUGAAGGCUCAGAUGACUGUUAGCAUUUUUUAGCAAAAGUAUUUUUAAAUUAAGGUAUUCUAGGGUACCCGUUUUCCCCACUUCCUUUCUGUGUCUUGACCAAAAUCACAGUGACCCAGCCAGCUGUAGCCAUAGGUUUUCCUCAGCUGGCUUGAACCCAAACCAGCUUGAACAUUCCCAGGCACUGAUAAUAAUGUCUUGGUUUACUGGAAAGAAACUGACCCCGACCCUGAGCCGAAUUCCUUAAAUUUUCAUGUAAACUCCAUCCCCUCACCCCCUGGCUACAGACUAAUGUGGGUAAAACAUCCCUUUUCUCUUGCUGUCCAUCACAAUAAUACAUUGCAACACCCUGCAAGUUCCUUUAAUAAAUGUUUUGGACUGAUCACUCUGGCAUUUAGAGCUGCUUUCUUUGAAAUCUCAAACCAGCCCUGUCUUCAAAUGGUUUGGGGUACUCUGUUGUACGAAUUCUCCUGCUGCUGCUUUUAAGGCAACUCCAGCUAUGGGUUCAGUGGGACAAAACAGGUAUGUACAUUUUUUAGACAUAGUGCUAUGCACAUUUAACAGACAACAAUGUAGUGUAAAUGGGAAACCAAAAAAUGCAUGUGGCUUCCUUUAUUGUAAUACCUGUUUUAUUGUGGUGGUCUGGAGCUGAACUUGCAAUAUCUCCAAGGUAUGCCUAUGCUUAAAUCUCUAUGAACAUAUAAUUUGCAGUGCUUAAAUAUUGUUCAAAACUAAAACAUGCUCUAUAUUAAAAAGUGACUUAAUUUUCUUCCUUAAGACAUUGAUUUAAAGAUUUAUCAAAAGUCUUUUGAGUAAGUUUUGAUGAAUAAUCAAAAUGCUGUAGCAGAGCUACAUCCUAAUUUCUGUGGGAAAUUUAGACACAGAAAUUUCCAAUGAGCAAAUAAGCUUGUCACAACAAGCCUUUUAAGGAAUCUGGCCUAAGGACAAAGUCCAAAGGCCAAUAGCUGCCUGUGGGCUACUGUGUUUUGUUGAGUCAGACAUAUAGAAACAGUCACCCACCUAGGAGGGUACUACAGAUGUAAAUAUUUAUAUUAAUAAAUGAAUCCUGCUGGAUCAGAAGUAACAUCUUAUCAAGUCAUCAUAUCAAACCAUUUGAGGAAACCCUGACUAAGGAAUGAAGAAGUCCUACAAAGAGGAGGUCUCAAGUACCAAUCAGCAGCCAUUUGAUGAUGGCAGUUCCAGGGAGAAGAUGUCCAUCUAUAAGAAAGUGGUCCCUCAGCAGACACUGAAUCUGCUGGUGUCCUGAUCUUGAAUAUACCAGCCUCCAGAACUCCCCUAUUCAAGAUGGAGUCACUCUGGUUCAAAGGCCUCUAACACCAGCGUUCAGAUGAGCUGCUACUCCUCCGGAGGCAAUUUGAAGUUGAGGGUCUGUGGCGCAUGGGCACCCACCUGUUCCUGGCUGCUGGGUAGGUAACACAUGCAUGGGUGCAAAACAUGCUUCUGUGUCAUCUCACAUAGUGUGGUCAACAGAGAACACCUGGGCAGAAGAUGAGAGGCUCCUGGGGACUGGUCUGAGACAAGGUGCUGUAAAAGAAAACCUAUAUUAAAGUGGUUGGAAGUGCACAGACUGGUUGCUUCACCUGCAGCCAGAAUGCAAGACAGGUGCAAGUCAUCCCUGAGGAAGUAGUGACCAGCUGUGGAUGCUACGCUGAGGCCCUUCUUUAAGAGUGAUCUGAUGGCACUGGAUGUCUGCUGAGGCUUGUGUCUAGAAGGAAUGAAAGGAUGUGCCAACAACAGCAGUUGUCUCCUCGUUUUCAAAGCUCAGGCCUCAUGCUCAAUGGCACCUGUUUUGCAUGGAGACAAGCACAUGCAAGAAAAAGUUGUAAAAGUGGAAGCAAAUGUGGUCUCAGAAGAGGAUUGAGAAAAACUUAGGGAGUCAGGCGUAAACAAGCAUUUGUCAUUCGAUUCUUCUAGUGCAUUUCCAGCAUACUGUGCCUUGGGCAUGACACAUCAGAAUCUGAUGUUUAUCUUUUAUUACCUGCCAGACCCCUCUGGAAAAGCCUCUAUGGAAUUCAUCAUCUGCAGUCUUUGUUGUAGGUACACAUAUAAAUACAUGUUGAAUGCAUUUGUUGAGGAUAUUGUGGUUUCUAACGCUGAACUUAAAAAGUGUUGAGAUGAAUAAUGAAGAGGACCUUCUGCAGGAGGACUCAACAAGAGAUGAAGGCAAUGAGACUGAAGCCAACAGCAUGAACACAUUAAGAAGGACAAGGAAGAAAGUCACUAAACCAUAUGUUUGUUCAACUGAAGUGGGAGAAACGGAUAUGUCCAAUUCAAAUGAGAGGAUCAGAAACCAAAUGGUGUGCCACAAAUUAGGGAACACAAGCAAACCUAUCAUGGGACCUGGCUCUGCUGAGUCUCAUCUGUCAUAUGAUGACAAGGACUCUCAGGAUGAGACAACAGUGAUAAAACCUUUGCCCCCCAGAACAACAACCAAUGUUCCUGGAGGUGAAUUUAACCCAAACUCUGAUUGCAUGAGGGACAGCAGUCAAAUUUUGACCCCACCUCAACUCUCUUCUAGAAUGAAACACAUUAGACAAGCCAUGGCCAAAAAUCGCCUCCAGUUUGUACGAUUUGAAGCAACAGACCUCCACGGCGUGUCCAGGUCUAAGACUAUCCCUGCACACUUUUUUCAAGAGAAAGUGAGCCAUGGUGUUUGCAUGCCCCGAGGUUAUCUUGAAGUGAUACCAAAUCCAAAGGACAAUGAAAUGAAUAACAUAAGAGCCACAUGUUUUAAUAGCGACAUAGUCCUAAUGCCAGAGUUAUCAACCUUUAGAGUUUUGCCAUGGGCUGACAGAACUGCAAGAGUGAUAUGUGAUACCUUCACUGUGACUGGUGAGCCUCUUUUGACUUCCCCAAGGUACAUUGCAAAGAGGCAGCUGAGCCAUCUGCAGGCCUCUGGCUUUUCCCUGCUUUCUGCUUUCAUCUAUGAUUUUUGCAUUUUUGGUGUGCCCGAAAUUUUAAAUUCAAAGAUUAUAUCUUUUCCUGCUUUAACAUUUUUAAAUAACCAUGAUCAGCCCUUCAUGCAGGAACUUGUUGAUGGCUUGUAUCACACUGGAGCCAAUGUCGAGAGUUUUUCCUCCUCUACCAGGCCUGGUCAGAUGGAAAUCUCUUUCCUGCCUGAAUUUGGCAUUAGCUCAGCUGAUAAUGCAUUUACCCUCAGAACAGGUGUCAAAGAAGUGGCAAGGAAAUAUAAUUACAUUGCCAGCUUCUUCAUUGAGACUGGAUUUUGUGAUUCAGGGAUUUUGUCUCAUAGUCUCUGGGAUGUCGAUAGGAAGAAAAACAUGUUCUGCAGCACUUCUGGAACUGAGCAGCUCACGAUCACUGGGAAAAAAUGGUUGGCAGGACUCUUGAAGCACUCUGCUGCGCUCAGCUGCCUGAUGGCGCCUUCUGUUAGCUGCCGAAAGCGUUAUUCCAAGGACAGGAAAGACCUGAAGAAGAGUGUGCCUACAACAUGGGGAUACAAUGACAACAGCUGUAUAUUUAAUAUCAAAUGUCAUGGAGAGAAAGGCACCCGGAUAGAAAAUAAACUAGGCUCAGCAACAGCAAACCCUUACUUGGUGCUGGCUGCAACUGUUGCUGCCGGCUUAGAUGGACUUCAUAGCAGUAAUGAGGUCUUGGCUGGUCCAGAUGAGAGCACAGACUUUUACCAAGUGGAACCUUCUGAGAUCCCUUUAAAACUAGAAGAUGCCCUUGUGGCACUGGAAGAAGAUCAAUGCCUGAGACAGGCUCUAGGAGAAACCUUUAUUCGAUAUUUUGUUGCCAUGAAGAAAUAUGAGUUGGAGAAUGAAGAAAUAGCUGCAGAGAGAAAUAAAUUCUUAGAGUAUUUUAUUUAGAAUAGAGCUCACAACUACUCCUUUAGACAUGUAAUUGUUACUUAAAGCUAAUCUACCAAAACAAAAAGACUGAACUUUUGUAAUUAACAACAGCAACAAUAACAAGAUUACGAAUGCUUUUGACUUUUUUUUUUGUCCAUGGAAUAUUUGACAGAUGAAGUAGGACUGCUGAGAAGAUUCUGAUAACAGAAACAAACAACAAAGUUGUGGUGAAGCUAUAAUAUGCAAACUUACCAGAUCUUGUCAGUCAUUUCCUAUGUGUAUGUUGACCUGGAUAAGAAUAUCCAAUUUUGGGUGGCAAUAAAUAUAUUCGCACAUUAAGAAAAAAAAGACUUAAGCAUUAGAAAGCAAAAUUUAAAUGACUAAAAAAGAAAAAAAAGAAAAGGAGAAAAAAUUUUAAUGGUACACAUAGGUUAUGAUUUCCAGGGAGACAAAUAUACUAAUAUAGUCUCGCUAAUCAAAUAAUAUUGUGAAUCCAGGUUGUAUGCACCAUUAUGGUCUUUCUAAACAAGUUAAAUAAACUUUUGCCAAAAUAUAAUGACAGGUAGGCAGUUUUCCCCUAAGUCUCUUCUCUUUUCACCCUUCUCCACUAGCUCCUGAAAAGCUUAUGAACUUCAAGGUUAUAAUGUCCUCAAGAAACAAAUCCCUAAGGAAUAGAAUUGGAGCUGAGAACAACGAGGUCAGAUUUUAAAAGUAGUUAAAGCCUUUCUUUUAACAAUGCCUCAUAUAGAAGUUCAAUACACAAAGUAUAGAUAGAAAGAUGUUUGUGUGUGAGGGUAGGUGGGCUCUGUCUACUCUGCUUCAUUCUUUGAAACUAGAUGUUCCUCUGAAACCUCUAGUGCUCUGUGGAGUGUGAGAACAACUGCCUGGCUAGCCAGGGCUAUGUUUGGAGUUUAAGUUUGUUAUUCAAAUUACUGAAUCUGCUGCUCACAGAGGUUGGUACCUCCCCAGAGAAUAUUACCUGUUCCAGGCCUUUGUUUGAAUGAGAUAAUAUUGUAACUAUCACAAAAGUUUAGCUGCUUUUGGGAAGAAGUCCAAAAUCCACUUACUAGCAAAUGAAACAUUAUUCUACUGCUUAGGAUCAAACAGCAGAUUUUAUGUUCAAUUAAAACUGACUGUAGUCUCAAUUUAGAUAGCAAUUGCACAAGCAGAGGAUUAGAAUUUGGCUCAGAUCCUCUUAUUAAAAUUCAUAUUACUCAGUAGCUUAAAUAGUGAAAGUCAGUCUAUCCUUCACUAAUUACUCCCUUCUUUUUUCCUUUGAGCAGGAGAAGUGUGUUUGGAUACAUAAGAAGAAAGUUCCCAGCACUUUGGGAGGCCAAGGCAGGAGGAUUGCUUGAGGCCAGGAGUUUGAGUCCAGCCUGGACCACAUAGUGAGACCCCUGUUUCUACAAAAAAAAAAAAAAAAAUGCCUCGCAUGGUGGCACAUGCCUGUAGUCCCAGCUACGUGGGAGGCUGAGAAGGGAGGAUCGCUUGAGCCUGGGAGUUUCAGGCUGCAGUGAGCCAUAAUCACACCACUGCACUCCAGCUUGGGUGACAGAGUGAGACACUGUCUUAAAAAAAAGAGAAGAAUAAAAUUCAUGGAUGCAUAUGGGGUAGAGAGAAAGAUAGUGUAGGGUAGCUGGGGGAAGGAAGGGAACCUGUCCUGAAACCUCCAGAAUGAAAUCCCACACAUUACAUCAUGGGAGGGAUAAGGAAGACUCUCAUGCCAAUUUUCUAGCUGUCUGCUAGAAAAUUCCCCUCUGUUCAUUUUCCCCUCUGUUCUCAGUAAUAAAACCUCAAUAUGUUCUUUGAAAGCAAUGAAAAAUGAAAUGAUAUUUCUGAGCCUUCAUUAAGGUUGGAUGUGGUCAUGUUAUUAGGUUCAGUGCAAAGAGGUGAAAGUAGAAGUGUUGCAUAUAAGUUCUUUAGGACAUUUUCUUUUCUUUUCUUGUAUUUUUUUUUUUUUUCCGAGAUGGAGUCUCGCUUUGUCACCCAGGCUGAAGUGCAAUGUGGGGGGGUCUUGGCUCACUGCAACCUCUGCCCCCUGGGUUCAAGUAAUUCUCCUGCCUCAGCCUCCCAAGUAGCUGGGAUCCCAGGUGCCUGCUACCAUGCCUGGCCUUUUAGUAGAGAUGGGGUUUCACCAUAUUGGCCAGUCUGGUCUUGAACUCCUGAACUCAGGUGAUCAGCCUGCCUUGGCCUCCCAAAGUGCUAGGAUUACAGGCAUGAGCCACCAUGCCCUACCACACUUUAGAACAUUUUUUUAAAUGACGGAUGCUGUGUGCUCUGCCCUUUCUUUCUCUUGCUGCCUUCACCCUUCCUGCUGAGUGGCCUACAGAUAAUGUGGCUAGGAUUAUGUCCUUGGGAAGGGAGGUUUGCUCCACAGGGUACAGUAAUAAGGUGGAAUCUCUGCUUUGUAGAGCAGUUUGACUUGCCUACAUCCAGAUGUUUACCUGAGAGAGAACCAAACUUCUAUCUUCUUUAAGCCACAAUGAUUUUGAUUCUUUGUUAGUUGCAAUGAAAUUUAUUUUCUCUUUUCCAUGUGUGUGUUGUAUGUGUGUUUGUGUGUGAGUGUGUGCAUAUGAGUGGGGAAUUUGAGGGAUUUGGGGAUGAAAGAACAAAGGUAUAAGAACCAGUGAAAGACGACUUCCUCAAUAUUCCCACUUCUAGAGAGGAUAAUCUGAGUUAAUCAAAGGGAUCCACACAUCCAAAAAAUGGGAUUGGCUCUAACCCAUCCCUAUAAAGUGGCAUAUCCCUUUAUAGUCCACGGGCCUUAAUGAAACAUGUCUAAUGCAUUGACUUCAUUUUACCAUAAUGAGUAAAGAUGCUGUAAAAAGUCUGAUAAUCACAGUGUUUGAAGCCGUUUUUUCCCCUUUCGCAUUAUUAGCAUAACUUAAAAACACAGUACUCAGGAUGCCAUGUGAAGGAAUUAUAUAACUAGGAAUAUUAUCUUCAGUAUUAAGUGUACAGUCGUGAGUCAAAGAAAAUAUUCAGCCAUAGAUUACAAAUCAGUUGAUAACGUAAGUUGGUGUGGCAGUUUCCACCAAGAUUUCAGUUAGGUGUGUGCUGAUGUAUAUUCUUGUUCUUUAAGGCAACCCAAAAAGAGGCAUUGGCCAGCAGAGUUCAGGGCCAAAGACAAAUUGGGGUAGGUACAUGUAAAAAUCAGUUAUCUAUUUUUCUAUUUCUUUCAUCUGUUCAUAGGCUUUCUAUUGUUGAAAGGACUUUCUGCUGAUGCUUCUACCUUCUUGGUCUGGGUUAAGAGGGUCAGACAUUCAUUCAGCAGCACUUAUUGAGCACCAUUUGUGUGCUAAGCCUUCAGCUGGGAGCCAUCAUACUAGGGGAGACCAAAACAAAGAUGAGCAGACAAUGAAAGAGUUUUGGAUCUGUGUAUCUUAAGCAGAACAUAAAUAAUUUUUUUUGUAGACCUAAUGCUGAAAAAAGCUAUUUGGAAAGCUUCUUUAUGGCUCGAAAAGGGUGCCUUAUAAAUAGCUUUACAAAAAUUGCUUUCUUAUUUUCAUUUACUAUAAUUGUUCUAAUCAAAGCUUAGGGGAAAAAUGUGAUUACUGAAUUUAAAGUUGGUAAUUAAAUGAGUAUACAUAAGAAAUGUAAAUUAAAAGCGAUAAUAUUUUAAGACUAGAAAUUAAAACAUUAGUAUUGUAGUAACAAGUUUCUAUUUUCAAGGACAUUCUAUAAUCUAAAAUUUCAUUUUACAGUGUGUGAAUAACAACAACGCUUGAAAUGAUUAUUUGAAGGCAAUGAAAGAUCAAAAAACUUUAAUCUGAAUAAAAAUUGAAAGCAUACAGUGAAGUCUGAGCUUAUCAGUAAAACAGAACAGUCUAUUGACAUAUCUCCAGUCACCUGUUUGACAAAAUACACUCACCAAUAUGUUUAUGAUAUAGGUAUGACUGGACAAUACCUUUAACCUUGGGUUUUCUAUGACAGGGGUAAGAAUUUGUGUCUUUAAACAUUACCUAUGUGCACAGUGCCUUCCCUGUUAAAGCUCUUCUCAUGCUGCCUAUAAUUAGGGGUUUACAUGAUACUUCCUAAUUGCUAAUUAGGAUGUGAAUUCUCAGAAUAAAAGGUACAGAUCUUACUUA